GUCACCACAGCAUCUGCUCACCAAUGCAAAGUAAGCAUGACUGCUCUCUUUCUGAUGUCCAUGCUUUUUGGCCUUACAUGUGGGCAAGCGAUGUCUUUUUGUAUUCCAACUGAGUAUACAAUGCACAUCGAAAGGAGAGAGUGUGCUUAUUGCCUAACCAUCAACACCACCAUCUGUGCUGGAUAUUGUAUGACACGGGAUAUCAAUGGCAAACUGUUUCUUCCCAAAUAUGCUCUGUCCCAGGAUGUUUGCACAUAUAGAGACUUCAUCUACAGGACUGUAGAAAUACCAGGAUGCCCACUCCAUGUUGCUCCCUAUUUUUCCUAUCCUGUUGCUUUAAGCUGUAAGUGUGGCAAGUGCAAUACUGACUAUAGUGACUGCAUACAUGAAGCCAUCAAGACAAACUACUGUACCAAACCUCAGAAGUCUUAUCUGGUAGGAUUUUCUGUCUAAUAGUGAUAUAAUUUGCAAUUUGGUUAAAUGUGCUUGCCUGAAAUAAAGCUAAUAAAAAUAUUAUGUUUCACAUUA